GGGUCUUGCUGUGUUGUCCAGGCUGGUCUCAAACUCCUGGCCUCAAGUGAUCCUCCAGCCUUGGCUUCCCAUAGUGCUGGGAUUGCAGGCAUGAGCCACCAUGUCCAGCUUGAAGAUAUAAUAUUGUAUCUAGGAUUUUCAAAUCCAUGUUGAAAACUGGGCCUUGAUUGGUUGAGUCAAGUGAGCUGAUUGGUUGAUUCAGGCGAAAGCAACAACAAUCAAAGAAGCCUUAGCGAGAUGGGAAGAGAAAACUGGCCAGAGGCCAUCUGAAGCCAAAGAGAUAAAACUUUAUGCCCAGAUUCCCCCUAUAGAGAAGAUGGAUGCAUCCUUGUCCAUGCUUGCUAAUUGCGAGAAGCUUUCACUGUCUACAAACUGCAUUGAAAAAAUUGCCAACCUGAAUGGCUUAAAAAACUUGAGGAUAUUAUCUUUAGGAAGAAACAACAUAAAGAACUUAAAUGGACUGGAGGCAGUAGGGGACACAUUAGAAGAACUGUGGAUCUCCUACAAUUUUAUUGAGAAGUUGAAAGGGAUCCACAUAAUGAAGAAAUUGAAGAUUCUCUACAUGUCUAAUAACCUGGUAAAAGACUGGGCUGAGUUUGUGAAGCUGGCAGAACUGCCAUGCCUCGAAGACCUGGUGUUUGUAGGCAAUCCCUUGGAAGAGAAACAUUCUGCUGAGAAUAACUGGAUUGAAGAAGCAACCAAGAGAGUGCCCAAACUGAAAAAGCUGGAUGGUACUCCAGUAAUUAAAGGGGAUGAGGAAGAAGACAACUAAUGCCACGCUUUCCACUGUGUGUUAACUUAUUUAAAUGUCAUAAGAACAAUAGAUAAAUUUUAUAUAAUUGUCUAUUUUAAAGAUUCUGUAUGGGACAAAAGUUUCUUAAGAUAAAACAGAUCACUCAUUCUCAUCUUUUUUUUUCCUUUAACUUAUUCAGUGUUUCUCCCCAAAACUGGUAAUGCCAACCUUAUAUAUCCUAUUUCUCUUUUUAGAAACCACAAAUUUUCGAUUUUUGUCUUCAGUCUCAGUUACGUACUGUGUAGCCCCAUCUACUAAAACAAAACCUUUGUAGACCAGUCAUUUUUAAUAACAAAGGAACAAAUGUUUUUUUCAGUUUGUUCAUUUUUUUUAGGUUAGACAUUUUAAAAGAUGUACAUUUGAAAAUUCAGAACAUUUUUCCUGAAGGUCUGUCUCUGUACAAUUCAGAAGCACAUGCCUUUAGCUCAGAAGGCAGCAUGGUGAUGGGAAGAGUUCCUCUUAGAAAUACAGCAGGUCCGGAACCAAGACUCCAAAGUUCCAUUGGAAAAGAUAUGGUGAAAAAAGGAAAAAGUAGUAUCUCAGAGACCUUCUAGUCUAUAUUAUACUUAUUUGUUUUUCCAAAAAUGUGCACAUUGUCAACUGGAAUUUAGGUUGUUUUUAUAUGCAUGGCCACUUGAGUCAUUGUGUACAGUCAUUCUGUGAUCUCAGUUAGUGGUUAAAAUGACUGUCAUGAUCAUUUCUUUGACUGAUAAUGUGGCAAUGUUACUCAUGUGGACCUCGCCUUAAGCACACAUUUUGGUUUUAUAGUUCCUUAUGUGUUUAAAGCAUUAGUUAUAUUUGAAUUCCUAGACUAAAUGCUGGCCAUUGAUGUAUGUCAAAAUUUACCCUAAUUAUUUGGUCUGGUGACCCUCAUUGUUGGGAAAAGUGACUACCAUGGUUAUAAGUAAGGGUAUAAUGAAACUUAGUAUUUCAAAAUAUAUUUUUUGAGAAGUUCUAAGUUAAACAGCUCUUAAAAUGUAUUAUGUACGUGGUUGUGGAGGGAAGGGAGAUGUUUCAUUAUGAGAUCCCAGGCAAAUGGCAAUAUGUUUGAGGAUUGUCUCCUACAUAAAGCAGUGUAGGUGAUUUAACCUCAAAAUUGCAAAGCAAUAGUUAGAUGCAGAGGUUAGAAUUUAUCAUGUAAACAAAAAAUCCUUCAGGAAAAUGUAAGACAUUGUAGUCAGUAAGCAGAUGAGGUCAUAGGAGGCCAUGGCUGGAUCACUAUUAGAUUGCAGAAAAGAAGUCAGGGGCCCUCUGCCAAAUUGUGCCUAAAGUCCCUCAGAGACUGUUGAUUCUGGUUUCCCCAUCUACUUGUGUGAUUUUACUUGCAUAAAAUCACAGUGAAAGAGGGAAGAAUCAUCUUUAAAAAGUGAUUGCAUAAGUAGUCCUGGGUUUCAGAAGAUUUCAGCUAUCAUUUACAUAGGAAUUACUUGAUUUUUCUAAGUUACUCUGAUCAAAAGGGACCACUGCUUUGACAAUCAACUCUAAAUACAAACAAGAGGCCAGGCGUGGUGGCUCAUGCCUGUCAUCCCAGCACUUUGGGAGGCCGAGGCGGGCGGAUCAUCUGAGAUCAGGAGUUCAAGACCAGCCUGACCAACAUGGUGAAACCCCGUCUCUACUAAAAAUACAAAAAUUAGCCAGUCCUGGUGGUGGGCGCCUGUAGUCCCAACUACUCGGGAGGCUGAGGCAGGAGAAUCAUUUGAACCCGGGAGGCGGAGGUUGCAGUGAGCCGAGAUUGCGCCAUUGCACUCCAGCCUGGGCAAUAGAGCGAGACUCCAUAUUUAAAAAAAAAAAAAAAAAAAAAAGAGGAAAACUUGGUCUAACACCCUUUUAGUUUUCUUUUCUCUCUUCUUUUCAAUCUGAUAGGAAGAAACCUUAUUCUACUCUAGCUGGUUUAUGCAUUCAAAGCCUUUGGACAUUUCUUUUAUGAACCAUAGGCAAUGAGCCUUCAUUCUCCUUGGUGAUGUUUUAAGUUCCAUAAACUGAGAGGGAAGAUGAUCUUCUUAAAGUUUGCACUUCCUUCAGUAGGCAAGCUUGAAGCCAUGUUGAUAUGGAUAUGUUUUCUAAAAGUAACCCUGGAAGUGAAUAUAAUAGGAAGUAAGUGAUUUCAUAUUGAAUUUAUUUGUAAAAUGGCUUAGAGUUUUGGUGUUUGUUUUUUCUGAAUUCUGUAAUAUAGAAACUGGUUCUCUUUCUCCUUGUUUCUCAAUGACUUUUAAUUACAGGUAGUUCUCAGACAAAUGUAAGAUACUUUUCUCUGUCCAUUUCAUGCAAAAUUCAUAUUCAGUAUCAUUCAACAAAUCUUUGAAUGACUUCUAUGCAUCCCUGUUCAUGGAACCCAUGCCAUUAGAAAAUGGCAGUUGGGAUGUAUGAAGAAAUGUAGGAUAUUCUCUCAAAUCAUUCCCUAAAUUAUCCUUUACUGCUGCAAAUUUAGCUGAUAAAACUGCCUUUGGUUUAUGCCUCUUGGAUCAGAUAUUUGACCUAUGUGGAAUAGAUUAUCUCUGUGCUUCCGGUUUAAGACAUUACGCCAUUUUAGUGGAUCAUUUAAAUUUUUUCUAUUCUGUUUUUUUUUGUUUGUUUGUUUGUUUGUUUUAAACAGAGUCUCACUCCCGAGUAGCUGGGACCACAGGCACGUGCCAUCAUGCCUGGCCUAUUUUUGUAUUUUUAGUAGAGAUGGGGUUUCACCAUGUUGGCCAGGCUUGUCUUGAACUCCUAACUUCAGAUGACCUGCCCACAUCGGCCUCCCAAAGUGCUGGGAUUACAGGCAUGAGCCACCGUGCCUGGCCAAAUUUCUUCUAUUCUUGUAAGUGAUGGUAAAACUCUGGAAUCAGUCCAGUAUUUUAGUUUUUCACAGCAAAUUUGAUUUUAGUCUACCAAGGAGUUUAACUUUUCUAUGUUCCCUAACUCUAAGAUUAGGGCUGUAUUACCUAGACAGGCCUUAAAAGGUUUUUGUGUUGUUCUCUGUUAAUAAGAAUUUGUUCCUUUAAACCAGAGGAUCAACCUUGGAACUAUUAACAUUUUGGGAUUGAUAAUUCAUUGUUGUUGGGGGCUGUCCUGUGUGCUUAGGAUGUUCAGCUGCAGCCCUGGCCUCUACCCACUAGAUUCCAGUAGACCCCCUCCUCAGCCAUGACAACAAAGAUAUCUCCAGACAUUGCCAUCUGUCCCUUGGGUAGGAGGGUGGGAACAAAUUCUCCCUUAGUUGUACUUUUUAUACCAACAUCACUUGUGUCCAGGGUCCAUUUAUUUUCAGUCUGUAGCCAUGUGCCACUUGAAUUGUUAUAUGAGAGAAGGUGAUGUAUUCAGUAAUCAUGGAUGGAAAGAAAUGGUCACUGGUAUUUUUUGUAAUGCUCAUUUUUUUUUUUUUUUGAGACAGAGUCUCGCUCUGUUACCUAGGCUGGAGUGCAGUGGCGCAAUCUCAGCUCACUGCAACCUCCGUCUCCCGGGUUCAAGCAAUUCUUCUGCCUCCGCCUCCCAAGUAGCUGGGACUACAGGCACGCGCCACCAUGCCUGGCUAAUUUUUGUAUUUUUAGUACAGACGGCGUUUCACCAUAUUGGCCAGGCUGGUCUCAAACUCCUGACCUCGUGAUCCGCCUGCCUCAGCCUCCCAAAGUGCUGGGAUUACAGACGUGAGCCACUGCGACUGGCUUAAUGCUCAUUUUCAUAAUUUUCAUGUAAUAUUAGAAACUCAGGGCUGGAAGGUUCAACUUCUCUUUUUUGAAGCAGGGUCUCAACUUUUAUUUCUAAGCAUUCUUGCUUAUCUUAGGACAGUGAUUAUUAACCUACCUCUCUGUUUCUAUCAACAGAAGCCAACUUUAUGAUAGAUUUUGCUUUGUCUCUAAAGUUUAAUAUUUUGAGUGUACUUUAGAAAAUAGGUCAUCAUUCUUUAAGCGUCAUUCAUUGUCUAAUCACAUAAUUUUGCAGACCAUGGCAGUCAUUAAAUACAGAAAAAUACUGUGUAAAAUUUGAUAAUCUUGUAGGAAAGUUAGCUGAUGUAGACAUCAAUUUUGGAUGUGAUCAGAAGAAUGUCUGCUUAAGAUAACUGGUCAAUAACUUGGUAUGGCUACUGGAUUCAUUCCACAUAUGGUAGUAUAAGGCACUUAAAUGUGUUUCCUGAUUGGGCACUGUGGCUCAUGCCUGUAAUCCCAGCACUUUGGGAGGCCGUGGUGGGCAGAUCACUUGAGGUCAGGAGUUCGAGGCCAGCCUGGCCAACGUGGUGAAACCCCAUGUCUACCAAAAAUAUAAAAAGAUAGCCGGGCGUGGUGGCGCAUGCCUGUAAUCCCAGCUACUCGGGAGGCUGAGGCAGGAGAAUUGCUUGAACCCGGGAGGCAGAGGCUUCAGUGAGCCGAAAUAGUGUGACUGUACUCCAGCCUGGGUGACAGAGUAAGUCUCCGUCUCAAAAAGAAAAAAAAAAAUGUGGUUCUUUUGUGGAAAGAGGAAUUUGAACUUGAAUAAACACUUCUUUUGACACCUUUUACCAGUGGUCUGAAGCAGAAUAAGGAAGAAUAAGAAAUGAAUCUUGACUGUUGACUUAUUCUGAGAAUUGGUGAUGUGUAAAGAGAGUUGGAAUCUUCUACCUGGGUUUUUCUCAGGGCUAAAUGGAAAAGCACAGGGCCCAGAAAGGUUGGAGUUAAUCAUUCACUUAAAAGCAUUAGGAGGAAGUGUCAAAGCAUCAGUCAUGAAUAGAUUAUGUCUCUCUGACUACAGUCAGACCAUCAAUUCACUAAGACCUUAUACUCUGUAAGUGUUGGUAAAGGAAGAAAACUGCUAAAUUGCAUGUUACCCUUUACUAGAAAUUCAUUCCUUUGGCACAGAUUUUAUUUAUUUGGGGCUGUUUAAUGUGUCUGUAAAUCAUGAAAUAUAAAAGCAAGAUUCAGUGUAGCAGAGUUGGUGCUUCUUCUGACAAGCUAACUUGACCAUAUUUCUUUAUCUGUGCUCUAACAUGUGUCAUAUUGUUUUCUUUUUGUAAACCAUAAAAUGGGUGAACUUCCAAAAAUCAAGGGUCAUGUUUUAAAAUCAUGGAACUUUUAGAAAUACCAUAUCUGUAUCUCUAUUCCUGCAUUUUAUAAAUCUGUAAAGGAAGAAAACUGAAAGGAAGAACUAGACUGAGUCUUACCUUUCUCUGACCUAAGAUAAACUGAUAAAACUUUUUACUUGAUAUUUGGAGAAGUCAUUAACUGGAUUCUAGUUAAUUUCCCAUAUUGGGCAGUUUAGAGGAGACCCAGCCAACCAAAUUAUGAUCUAGCAAAUUUAACAUAGGGGAAGAGGGAUAGUAAACUAUUUUUCAGUAGAUUUGCACUUUAAACUUAGGAACUGGAUGUUGGUGGAAAGGACUUCCAUAGGGCAGAUGGGUAAAUAUCUAGCCUGCACUUGGAUGUUAGAGAAUCAAACCUCACCCUUGCUCGUUCUAAACCCACAUGAGUAGUUAACUGUCUUUUGACAUAAUCAGAGUCAGGAUUUCCCUUUUUCCCUACUUGAGUCGUCUUCCAUGUCUGUUACAUCCAAGAUCAUCCCUCUGGGGGAUGUGUCAAGUAGUUCUCCUACUCAGAAUAGAAGCUUUGCGAAUUAUCAUUCCCACCUCUAGAUUUUAAAUGAAUGUAGAGUUGUCUAACAUUAUAUGGGUGGGAGGCUCUUUGCCUCUGUGAUCAGUAGGGUACCUGCCUCUGAGGUGCUACUGCCUGGAGGGAUCACUCCCAUCAAAAGACUGGUGAGUUGGAAGCUAAGAGCACAUGCGCAUAGCCAGCUCCUCUCCCAGGCUGGCAGUCAUGAUUACGAGCAUCAUUCCAGAAUCUUUGGCUUCUAGAACCAACUCCAUUCUGAAGAACAUUUUAACAUCUAUGAAUACCUUGGUAAUAAUCUUUUAUACACAGGAGUUUUGUAGCAUGACUUUAUGACUAAACUUAUUGUGAAUUAAGUUAUUUAGAAAUGUUGAGUUUCUGAAUGUUAUUUUGUGAUUUGUUUCAAAAUGGUAAUAAAUUGUGUUAUUUUGUAAAAAAAAAAAAAAGUAUAUUUUUGGUACAUGAUUAUUAGUUUUAGCUAAUAUAGAGCAAUUAUAUAAACUUCUAGUGAUAUUCAGUCCAAAGAAAUUCAGCCUUUGGAUAACAUGUACCAUGCAGUUUGUGUGGUGUGUGUGUGUGUGUGUGUGUGUGUGCACGUGCAUGAGAGAGAGUGAAAGAGAGAGGUGUUUUUUGUUUUGUUUUUUUUGAGACGGAGUCUCACUCUGUUGCCCAGGCUGGAGUGCACUGGCACAAUCUCGGCUUACUGCAACCUCCACCUCCCGUGUUCAAGCGAGUCUCCUGCCUCAGCCUCCCGAGUACUGGGACUACAGGCGCACACCACCAUGCUUGGCUAAUUUUUGUAUUUUUAGUAGAGACGAAGUUUCACCAUGCUGGCCAGGUUGGUCUCGAACUCUUGACCUCGUGAUCUGCCCGCCACAGCCUCCCAAAGAGCUAGGAUUACAGGCACGAGCCACCGCGCACGGCCAGAGGCAUUCAUUUCUUUAGCUAAGUUUUUUUUUCUUAGUAGGUUUUUUUCUCCCAGGCUUGUAACUCUUCCCCAGUUCUUUGGGCACUAUUUCAAAUUAUUAGGCUUCUGGAAAGAGUGCUUCCAGGGACAGCAAGUUACUACUGCACUUGACCAUUCCUAGUCCUCACCUGAUUACCAGAAGGUACGCAAGGUAAAAGUUAGCUGAUAGGCCCUGAAUUGAGAAAAAGGAAUCACCAAGCAAUAUCCGUAACAUUACACAUUUUGCCAGCACAUUUUCUAUGCUAUCAGCUAAAACGUAAUUUUGGUCACAAAAUAGGGCUGUAGUGUAGUUUCUACUUCUUAUUCCAGUUGUUUGAUUAUGAGGAUACAUUUCUUGCUGCUGUCCUCCACUAAACAGCAGACAAAUUGCCAGGUGUGCUGGCUCAUGCCUGUAAUCCCAGUGCUUUGGGAGGCCAAGGCAGGAGUUUGAGACCAGCCUAGGCAACAUCGUGAGACCCCAUCUCUACAAAAAAAAAAAAAGAAAAAAAAAAUUAGUUGGGCAUGGCAAUGCCGCCUGUGGUCCUAGCUACUGGGGAGGCUGAGGCAGGAUUGCUUGAACCCAGAAGUUUGAGGUUACAGUGAGCUAUGAUCAUGUCACUGCAAGACCCUGUCCCUAAAAAAAGGAAAAACAAAUAGAAGACAAAUUUCAAUUUCUGAGUUUAUACAAAGAAAGCCUUAAUUCAGAUCAUAAAUAUCCCAUUGUUAUUUUUAGUUCAUUGUUUCCUAGAACAAAGGAUGGACAUUUAGGAUCCUCACAUUGAUUUAUGUCAUAUAUAUGUAUUGCAUUGAAUAUAUAUAUACGCAUGUAGAUACAUACAAUUGUUAUAUAUAAUUAAAAGUCAGAAUCUUAGGUGAUAACUGUCAGACCUCUGAGCCCAAGCUAAGCCAUCGCAUCCCCUGUGACUUGCACGUAUACAUCCAGAUGGCCUGAAGUAACUGAAGAUCCACAAAAGAAGUAAAAAUAGCCUUAACUGAUGACAUUCCACCAUUGUGAUUUGUUCCUGCCCCACCCUAACUGAUCAAUGUACUUUGUAAUCUCCCCCACCCUUAAGAAGGUUCUUUUUAAUUCUCCCCACCCUUGAGAAUGUACUUUGUGAGCUCCACCCACUGUCUGCAAAACAUUGCUCUUAACUUCAGCGCCUAUCCCAAAACCUAUAAGAACUGAUGAUAAUCCACCACCCUUUGCUGACUCUCUUUUCGGACUCAGCCCGCCUGCACCCAGGUGAAAUAAACAGCCAUGUUACUCACACAAA